GGGGACGCGCAGGCGGGUGGGUUUCAGCGCCUGGGCCCCUCUCCCCGCCGCGGGGCGCACGGAAAAACCGGGGAACCCGCGGGUUUUGUCCUGGCGAGCCACAUCCCGGUGUGUUUUGGCGACUUGAAGACCUCCCUAGUUCGCGGGAGUAGCGGGAAGAGCCUUCCUCGCGUUAAUUAUGCAAUAAGAAGGCGUCCUUGUGCGGGAUGCUGUGACCCGCGGAAUUAUUGAUAUUGUGCGAGCCUACAAUUUACUUCUUUCAUCCUUGGCUGAGAAUUUGCGUUUGUAAUUGUAGAUGGAGAGAGGAAGAAAGGGUUCAGCUUGGGUCCAAGGAGCAUGCAGAGGAAGGCAGGGAAGAAGGAGCAUGUGCAGCUUCGGUGCGAGGGGAGUCAGGGGUGGGAAUGCACGUUCCCUGCCUGAGGGGCCCCGGGGUGCCCUGAGCCUCUGAUCUUCGCUGUCAGGAGGCCUGUCCGAAGUUGGAGGUUGAGGCAUGCAGUUCUGCACUUCUGGCUGGGAAGGUGAACCAGGUUUUCCAAAAUGUCAUUUUUGCUUUCCAAGUCUGCAAGGCAGGAAAGGGUUGGGCAGUGAAUGGAAAGUAGUGCAGCCAGGUUCUGGUUAGCUCAGCGGCAGGACUGUCAUAACGGUGGGUUUUUGUUGUUGUUGUUGUUGUUGUUGUUUUGUCUGAAAACCAGAGUCUGGGGCUUUGGGCCAUGAGGAGUUGGGUUAUUGCAUUGCUUAGAGUGCCAGAGUGAGAAAUGUCUCAGACGCUGUUAAAAUUAGGCAGCUCAGUUUAGCUCUGGCUCUCUGAUAACCAACCACCUCCUCCUUCACUCUUUUCAGUGACUGGGUUAAAAUGAAAAGACACAAAGAGAGAAGUGGUCUUUUCCCUUCCCUCCCCAUUAUAAUUAAGAGCUUAGUCCAUCUUGGCUCAGAAUUGGAAUUCAGAAUUCAGAAUUGCUCUUGACCCUGAAGAAUAGAAUCUCAAAGAAAUACCUGAGCAGAAAAUUCUCUUCUUCGCUGAAAUGAAAAUUGGAGUGUUUGCAAAACUGAACAAAGAAAGGAAAGAAUUUGUAAACAUCACAGGCAACUUGCAGUUAUAUUCGGAUCAUUUUUCAGUGUUUGAGGAGUUCAUACAAUAAAAAGUGACAAGAGGAACCAAGAACCUCAGUUCAGGGGAAACACAGCAAGGAAAUGUGAGCCCCAGGCUGCAGAAGACCCUACUGUCGCAUUAAUUUCUGGCAACCACACUGAGAAAGGUGUAGAUUAAGCUGGAAAAUCACGAAGAGUGCCAAGGGAUUGGUCAGUUUUUACUGGGGGUCUGCACCAGGCCAGAUGCCUGGUUCCUGUGAGAUUCUAGGAUGUAAAUGUUGAGACAAGGAGAGUGAUUCACCUGGGUCUUCAUGGAGCUCUGACCCACCCAGGGUUAGGAGGCUCUCUCUGAAAUUAUUUGCCAUCAGCACUGUGUUGAGGGGACCACUUCUCCCUGCCAUGCAGAAGUGAUGGAUGGCCUCAGUCAGUCGGUGGAAGCCAGCUCAGCCCAGGGUCUUGUCUGUACGUGGAGAGCUUUGGCUUGAAGAAGCACUGUGUUAAAGGAAGAGUCAGUGAAUGGCUGCGGUGUGACAACAUGCACCACCAGUGGCUUCUGCUGGCCGCAUGCUUUUGGGUGAUUUUCAUGUUCAUGGUGGCUAGCAAGUUCAUCACGUUGACCUUUAAAGACCCAGAUGUGUACAGUGCCAAACAGGAGUUUCUGUUCCUGACAACCAUGCCGGAAGUGAGGAAGUUGCCAGAAGAGAAGCACAUUCCUGAGGAACUGAAGCCAACUGGGAAGGAGCUUCCAGACAGCCAGCUCGUUCAGCCCCUGGUCUACAUGGAGCGCCUGGAACUCAUCAGAAACGUCUGCAGGGAUGAUGCCCUGAAGAAUCUCUCGCACACUCCUGUCUCCAAGUUUGUCCUGGACCGAAUAUUUGUCUGUGACAAGCACAAGAUUCUUUUCUGCCAGACUCCCAAAGUGGGCAACACCCAGUGGAAGAAAGUGCUGAUUGUUCUAAAUGGAGCAUUUUCUUCCAUUGAGGAGAUCCCCGAAAACGUGGUGCACGACCACGAGAAGAACGGCCUUCCUCGGCUCUCUUCCUUCAGUGAUGCAGAAAUUCAGAAGCGAUUGAAAACAUACUUCAAGUUUUUUAUUGUAAGAGAUCCCUUCGAAAGACUUAUUUCUGCAUUUAAGGAUAAAUUUGUUCACAAUCCCCGGUUUGAGCCUUGGUACAGGCAUGAGAUUGCUCCUGGCAUCAUCAGAAAAUACAGGAGGAACCGGACAGAGACCCGGGGGAUCCAGUUUGAAGAUUUCGUGCGCUACCUCGGCGAUCCGAACCACAGAUGGCUAGACCUUCAGUUUGGGGACCACAUCAUUCACUGGGUGACGUAUGUAGAGCUCUGUGCUCCCUGUGAGAUAAUGUACAGUGUGAUUGGACACCACGAGACCCUGGAGGACGAUGCCCCAUACAUCUUAAAAGAGGCUGGCAUUGACCACCUGGUGUCAUACCCGACUAUCCCUCCGGGCAUUACCGUGUAUAACAGAACCAAGGUGGAGCACUAUUUCCUGGGCAUCAGCAAACGAGACAUCCGACGCCUGUAUGCCCGUUUCGAAGGGGACUUUAAGCUCUUUGGGUACCAGAAACCAGACUUUUUGCUAAACUAAUGCAUAAGACCUAUGAAUUCAAAUAUCUUUAUUAGACCUGGGGCUAACCAGGUGAAGAUCUGAGCCCAGAAAUGACCCUUCCUCCACCACACCCCUCCUUUGAGGACGCCCGGGGUCUCCCACAGGCCUGUGAGUUGCCUCGGCAUAUGACGCAGAACCCCAACUGUUACAACUUAGUUUGGAUGUAAGAUGCUCUGAGGACCCUGCCCACACCCCUGCGUGCAUUAGGAUGUCGCUGGCCUUUGCUCACCUCAGAGGGGAGAAAAGGCUAAAGAUUUGCAGUUUGACAGCCCAGCAGGGAGGAAGCAUCACACAGCGUUAGGAGCCGUUUCCUUCAGGUGUUAAGGAAGGGGAUGCCCCUGAGGUUCUCCUGGCUAGUCAGGGUGGCUUCACCCAUCACUGGUGGGUUGCAGGAACAGCACCCAGGACUCUGAGGAGGGACAGAGAAGCAAGGGGGCUGCUGAAAUCGCAGAGACUUUUGCAGCAUCAGAUCUGAGGAGUAAAACGGCACCUCUGGCCUUCAUCUUGGUGCUGCGACAAUUGUGGAGGCAAAGCAUUCUUUCUGUGACUAUUUUGUUCCUGUAGACAGUCAGCGAUGGCCAGAGGGUGGUGUGGUGUCCAGGGGUCCAUCUUUCCAGAAUCCAUGCCUGUGUAAUGCUGGUCCAUGCUUCUGAACCUGUGUCUGCCAAGCGCCUAUUUCAUUCAGCACAAGACAUACGAUUUUAGAAGGUGAGGGGAGGGGAGGCUUUUUCUACCUGAGAAGGGGAGUGUCUUUGAGGGCCUUAAAAGGACCAUGGCCCAGGAAUGGGGGCGCUGGUUGGGCUUGGAGCUCAGGCUGCUGUGGAUCCCGGCGCAUCAGUUCUGACUUGCCUUACCUGGGUGGACAGCAGUGAAUCUCCACCUGUCUUCUCCAGGGAGCUCCCAUGUUGGGGCUGAAGACGAGCAGGGGCAACCUGCCAGCAUCACAGAAUUCAGUGUAGUUUAUACAUUUCGAUUCCUUUCAUCUCAGCAAAAUGGGCACUGCCAGAGCCAUUUCUGAUCACACCACCAUCCUGGACCAUGUGACUGGAAGGUGGGUAACCAAGUUCACCAGCAAUAAAACCCAGCGCCCAGGUAGCCUCCAGCAGUGCGGCUUCCUGGCAACAAGGUAGGCCCUGGUGCAGGGCAAGCCGCAGCGACCAUUUCAGAUACCGUCCACAGCCAGGACCGCUGAGAACUGGGACAGUUUCCUGGGAUGAGUGCCAGCCUGAGCCUGCAUGGUGCCGCCGAGCCCGGGGUGGAGGAGGGAGCCAGGCUUCGCUUCAAGGCGGCCUCUACCUUUUCUCAGAAUGGUUUCCUGAUUGUGUCAAUGUGAAAGUUAAAUAAAAUUUAUGUGCCAAACCUGA